AUGCGUAGACACACACAUCCUUACUCUGCGCGCAUCCCUGGCCUGGUGGACGGAAGAUCGAGCGCUCUGGGUGGACUUACGGCCACAGGACGGGGGCAGAGUCGGCAGGGAGGCCCCUCCGAGGCCCAGUGGGCCCUGCGCUGGCCCCGGCCGCAGACGCCCACCUGCUGCUGUGCUGGCUGCGGCCGCCGCCUGCUGGCCACAGAGAGCCCACGUGCGCCGGCCGCCAGGCCUGGGCAUCUCCCCUCCUGCAGCGCCGCCUGCUGGCCACAGAGAACCCGCGUGCGCCGGCCGCCAGGCCUGGGCAUCUCCUCUCCUGCAGCGCCGCCUGCUGGCCACAGAGAACCCGCGUGCGCCGGCCGCCAGGCCUGGGCAUCUCCUCUCCUGCAGCACCGCCUGCUGGCCACAGAGAACCCGCGUGCGCCGGCCGCCUGGCCUGGGCAUCUCCUCUCCUGCAGCGCCGCCUGCUGGCCACAGAGAACCCGCGUGCGCCGGCCGCCAGGCCUGGGCAUCUCCUCUCCUGCAGCACCGCCUGCUGGCCACAGAGAACCCGCGUGCGCCGGCCGCCUGGCCUGGGCAUCUCCUCUCCUGCAGCGCCGCCUGCUGGCCACAGAGAACCCGCGUGCGCCGGCCGCCAGGCCUGGGCAUCUCCUCUCCUGCAGCGCCGCCUGCUGGCCACAGAGAACCCGCGUGCGCCGGCCGCCAGGCCUGGGCAUCUCCUCUCCUGCAGCGCCGCCUGCUGGCCACAGAGAACCCGCGUGCGCCGGCCGCCAGGCCUGGGCAUCUCCUCUCCUGCAGCGCCGCCUGCUGGCCACAGAGAACCCGCGUGUGCCGCCAGGCCUGGGCAUCUCCUCUCCUGCAGCGCCGCCUGCUGGCCACAGAGAACCCGCGUGCGCCGGCCGCCAGGCCUGGGCAUCUCCUCUCCUGCAGCGCCGCCUGCUGGCCACAGAGAACCCGCGUGCGCCGGCCGCCAGGCCUGGGCAUCUCCUCUCCUGCAGCACCGCCUGCUGGCCACAGAGAACCCGCGUGCGCCGGCCGCCUGGCCUGGGCAUCUCCUCUCCUGCAGCGCCGCCUGCUGGCCACAGAGAACCCGCGUGCGCCGGCCGCCAGGCCUGGGCAUCUCCUCUCCUGCAGCGCCGCCUGCUGGCCACAGAGAACCCGCGUGCGCCGGCCGCCAGGCCUGGGCAUCUCCUCUCCUGCAGCGCCGCCUGCUGGCCACAGAGAACCCGCGUGCGCCGGCCGCCAGGCCUGGGCAUCUCCUCUCCUGCAGCGCCGCCUGCUGGCCACAGAGAACCCGCGUGUGCCGCCAGGCCUGGGCAUCUCCUCUCCUGCAGCGCCGCCUGCUGGCCACAGAGAACCCGCGUGCGCCGGCCGCCAGGCCUGGGCAUCUCCUCUCCUGCAGCGCCGCCUGCUGGCCACAGAGAACCCGCGUGCGCCGGCCGCCUGGCCUGGGCAUCUCCUCUCCUGCAGCGCCGCCUGCUGGCCACAGAGAACCCGCGUGCGCCGGCCGCCAGGCCUGGGCAUCUCCUCUCCUGCAGCGCCGCCUGCUGGCCACAGAGAACCCGCGUGUGCCGGCCGCCAGGCCUGGGCAUCUCCCCGGGCCCUAGUUCCCCCCCUCACCUAAGGGGAGGGACUCCCGUCUUUCCAUCCACCCCCUCCUUGCCUCUGCAGAGCUCCAGGGAAGGCUGGCACCCGCUCACUGCAUUUAGACUCCAUCAGGUUCAGACAGUGGGUCAGGGUACAAGGCUUCAGCGGCCAGGGAUGUGGCCUCUAAUUUGUAGAGAGAAAGAAGGACAGAGGCAAAGGUUUGGGCCCAGGGACUGGGCUCCGUUUCCAGAAUCACUCUUGGAGCUGCUCUGCUGCCCCCUGCCCCAUACACGUGAUGGAGCAGAAAACGUGCUGUGUGAACCUGUGACUUCAGGGCCUGUUGACGUGGUCGUGCUUGCAUACUCUCUGGACUGGACCUCACUGUGGGAACAACAAGAUCAACAAGAGGAGCAAGAACAACAUCAAGAGUCAGGGCCCGGGGGUCCUGACGGGUACAGGAUGGGUACAGACCCACACAGGAAUCCCAGAGUGUGUUCCACAGCAGGACACGCCUGCGCUGAAAGAGUGGGCAGAAAGGAGCUGACCUGGACCAAACCAAUGCACAACUCCUACGUACUGAUGGUGGUCUUACGUUUCCCUAAGUUUCUGCCGACUAAACUGUGCACACGUUCUCAGGACCUCCUGAAGCUGCGUCACAGGCGCUGAUCAAAGAACACAACCAAGAGUUUGGCCUUUUCUUCAGCACUGGGAAUUGUGAUCCAAAGCUUUUCCUGAUGAGGCACAAAGUUGGAGAAA